CUCUCUUCCUCUUUCCCCUCACUGGUAACAGAGCACUCCAAGGUUCUAGGGGAGGUUGGACCCCAAAGUUGGAAGAAUCUGGGCACCUGAGUCACCUGAUGGAGGAGCUCCAACUGCCAACCGGGGGCCCCCAUAUGGACGUGUCACCCAGUGAGAAGUGAGCCUUCCAUUGUGACAAACUGCAGGUAUUUCAAGGCUAAUUUGUUAAAAUCUACGGUUAAUAUGCUAUAUAUGACUUUUGAAUAGUCAGAGGUGUGCCCUCCACAUUAGACUGUGAGGUCCGUUGACUUGUGUGGCUCGUCUCUGACACAGACUCAAGCCCUUAAUAGGCGCCUGGAAACGUAUGUUUUCGUUCACACAAAAAGGAAGUUGACCAAGCCCCCUUGAUGAAGCCUCACUGGGGAGGUGGCCCAUCGAAGGUUGUAUAUUGUGAAUGGGGCGAAGGCAGCGUCGCCGUCUCCUUCAAGUCUGACCUCCAGGUUGGUGUUCAGAUUCCCCCUCCACACCCCACAGCCGUGGUUGCCCGUCUGGAUUUGGUGUUUGGGUCAGAGAUGACGUUCGGGCCGGGCGUAUGGAUGAUGAUGUCCAAGGAGACAGUUCUCUCCUUUACCCCAGUCACAGGAAGGAAGAACUAAGCCUCAUGGUGACUUCCUGGGAGAUACGUGGUAAGAAGCCACAAGACGGUUGGGACUGAGUCUCUGCGCACCGCAUCCUGAGCCUCUGCAUUCUGCACAGCGGGGCGGGCGCAGGCAGCACGGUGCCCCUUACCAUGCUUUCUUCCUGGACUUUCCCUUGACCAGUCUUGGCACGGCAGGCGAGGGAUUGAGGGAUUGGGGCUGGGAGGUGGGGAAGACAGCUCUCUCCCUGGGCCCAUGUCUGGUUAGAUCAAUGCUGUGGGAGCUUAGCGAUCGAAGAGGGAGCAGAGAUGACGGCGGGACGGCAUUGUCUGCCCAAGCCUCAGGCUUCGCAGCCCAGGCUGGGACCAAGAGCUUACAGACGUCAUCGAGUGCAGAUUUUGAGCGACGUACUGAGCAUUGUAAAUCCAGAUUUCUCUUCCAGAGCUGAGUCUGGGCCACAGGACCUGGACACAGGAGGGUCAGUCUUUCCGGUAAUGGUGAGGGUCUGUCUUCUUGGAGCAGCACAGCGGACUCCCACCAGGACAGUGGAUGCUGGGUACGGAAGGGCUGGGCUGAGGACAGUGGAUGCUGGGUACCGAAGGGCUGGGCUGAGGGGGUCACUUUGGCAGUGGUUCUGGAGUCUAAAUUUCUAAGGGCCUGGAACUCAGGAGACUCUAGAUGCUGAUUCUUUUCUGGAGAACUUCUCCAGAGUCACCAUCCUGGCUUGUGCAGACUCAACAUUCCACCUGAAGAGCUCUGGGAACCUCUGGGGCUGGGAGCCUUCUGGGCCUGAUGAGUUCUGUUGGGAUGGAGAAGAUGAUCUUGAAGUUAAAGAUUUCAGUGGGAGUCCAGGAAAACGUCGCAGCUGUCCAUCAUACCCACAACAGCAAACGACUCAGGACUUUGCCAAGGUCACUGCGGCAGCCAAAACCACAGCUGUGAUCUGGGGCCGGACUCAUACCCAGGGGUUGUCUGGGUUCAGGUUCUGCACCCCCGGUUCAGAGAAAGAGGAAACGGAGUGGGCCGUGUGGACCCCGUCCUUCAUCGAACUCCAGAACUAAGGGAACUGGGAGGGGAGAAGGCCGUCACCCUUGCACAGAGCUGCCUCCUUCAGUUCUAGUGGUUUCUACUCCUCUCUGCAGCCCCAUCCUGGGUAAAAUCGGAGACGUAUACAGGGCAGGGAGAAGCUGUUUAUUUCCGUGCCUGCGGCUGGAGCUUCUUAAGGAUUUGAGCUGUGAUGCUGGCACCUGGCAGACCACAUCCUGUGCGGUUUUCAGUUUUGCUCCGUUCCUGACCCUGGUAUAGCAGAAGCUUUUUCACAUCUAUGACACCCGCUAUGUCUUGGUAAACCCUGGAAGGGAAAGGAGGACAAGGUUAAAAUACUGUUCCGAGGACCUGGUCUCUCCACAGCGCAGGCUGGAGGUGGCAGCCCGUGGAAAGCCAAGUUCAUCCACCAUCGGAGCCCAGGCCAGGCUGCCAAGGCUAAUAUUCAGGACAAAGCCAGGCACAGGUCGGGAAUCCUAUGAAGAUGAUCAUCGUCCUGAGGUCUUCCUUCCAGGGUUGCAUCCGCGACAGAAGAUGGAAAGAGAAAUGGUGCUCUGCCUGGCCCAGACCAUCCACACGCAGGAGGAUCUGCCCAGACCCUCCAUCUCGGCUGAGCCAGGCACCGUGAUCCCCCUGGGGAGCCAUGUGACUUUCGUGUGCCGGGGCCCGGUUGGGGUUCAAACAUUCCGCCUGGAGAGGGACAGUAGAUCCACAUACAAUGAUACUGAAGAUGUGUCUCAAGCUAGUCCAUCUGAGUCAGAGGCCAGAUUCCGCAUUGACUCAGUAAGAGAAGGAAAUGCCGGGCUUUAUCGCUGCAUCUAUUAUAAGCCCCCUAAAUGGUCUGAGCAGAGUGACUACCUGGAGCUGCUGGUGAAAGAAAGCUCUGGAGGCCCGGACUCCCCGGACACAGAGCCCGGCUCCUCAGCUGGACCCACGCAGAGGCCGUCGGACAACAGUCACAAUGAGCAUGCACCUGCUUCCCAAGGCCUGAAAGCUGAGCAUCUGUAUAUUCUCAUCGGGGUCUCAGUGGUCUUCCUCUUCUGUCUCCUCCUCCUGGUCCUCUUCUGCCUCCAUCGCCAGAAUCAGAUAAAGCAGGGGCCCCCCAGAAGCAAGGACGAGGAGCAGAAGCCACAGCAGAGGCCUGACCUGGCUGUUGAUGUUCUAGAGAGGACAGCAGACAAGGCCACAGUCAAUGGACUUCCUGAGAAGGACAGAGAGACGGACACCUCGGCCCUGGCUGCAGGGAGUUCCCAGGAGGUGACGUAUGCUCAGCUGGACCACUGGGCCCUCACACAGAGGACAGCCCGGGCUGUGUCCCCACAGUCCACAAAGCCCAUGGCCGAGUCCAUCACGUAUGCAGCCGUUGCCAGACACUGACCCCAUACCCACCUGGCCUCUGCACCUGAGGGUAGAAAGUCACUCUAGGAAAAGCCUGAAGCAGCCAUUUGGAAGGCUUCCUGUUGGAUUCCUCUUCAUCUAGAAAGCCAGCCAGGCAGCUGUCCUGGAGACAAGAGCUGGAGACUGGAGGUUUCUAACCAGCAUCCAGAAGGUUCGUUAGCCAGGUGGUCCCUUCUACAAUCGAGCAGCUCCUUGGACAGACUGUUUCUCAGUUAUUUCCAGAGACCCAGCUACAGUUCCCUGGCUGUUUCUAGAGACCCAGCUUUAUUCACCUGACUGUUUCCAGAGACCCAGCUAAAGUCACCUGCCUGUUCUAAAGGCCCAGCUACAGCCAAUCAGCCGAUUUCCUGAGCAGUGAUGCCACCUCCAAGCUUGUCCUAGGUGUCUGCUGUGAACCUCCAGUGACCCCAGAGACUUUGCUGUAAUUAUCUGCCCUGCUGACCCUAAAGACCUUCCUAGAAGUCAAGAGCUAGCCUUGAGACUGUGCUAUACACACACAGCUGAGAGCCAAGCCCAGUUCUCUGGGUUGUGCUUUACUCCACGCAUCAAUAAAUAAUUUUGAAGGCCUCACAUCUGGCAGCCCCAGGCCUGGUCCUGGGUGCAUAGGUCUCUCGGACCCACUCUCUGCCUUCACAGUUGUUCAAAGCUGAGUGAGGGAAACAGGACUUACGAAAACGUGUCAGCGUUUUCUUUUUAAAAUUUAAUUGAUCAGGAUUGUACGUAUUCAAGGUGUAAAAUGUGAUAAUUUGUCGUACACGUACAUUGUGCAAUGACAGUCACAAUCAAUUCCUCAGCGCACCCAUCGCCACAGAUACGAUACAUUAGAUAUUCUGAACUUGCUCAUCUUAGGACUUCACAUUGGUGUCAGUGUUUUCUGACAAAUCACGUGUAUCAGGAAUGAAUGAGGGAGGUGUGGCUGGGUGAAGGCAGAGAGCCGACCCUACAGGUCCACAUCUGCACAUACAUGCACAGGAAUGCAUGCUCUCACACACAUGCAUACACACACGCACACACACAGACAUGCACAUACACUCACACGCCCCAGGAAAUCCAAGGAAUCACUGAGCCUGCUGUUGGUUGAGGCAUUUCUGAGUAUCCACCCUACCUGUAGGGUCAGAUGUACUGAUUGACACAGAAAAUUACCCUAUGUACCACUAGGAGGCGGCAGAAUCUCAUUUGGGUUAAUCUGUGUUUGUCUUUAAAAAACAAAAACAGGCCGGGCAUGGAGGCUCACGCCUGUAAUCCCAGCACUUUGGGAGGCUGAGGUGGGCGGAUCACGAGGUCAGGAGAUCGAGACCAUCCUGGCUAACACGGUGAAACCCCAUCUCUACUAAAAAUACAAAAAAAUUAGCCGGGUGUGGUGGUGGGUGCCUGUAGUCCCAGCUACUCGGGAGGCUGAGGGAGGAGAAUGGCGUGAACCCGGGAGGCGGAGUUUGCAGUGAGCCGAGGUGGUGCCACUGCACUCCAGCCUGGGCGACAGAGCGAGACUCCGUCAAAAAAGAAAAGAAAAGAAAAGAAAGAUUUUUAAGAAUUCAGCAAAAACUCAGCCAGCUCUUUCUAUGGGGCAGUUGCUAAUUUAGUUCUAGGCAAACGUGGACACAUUAAAUUCUCCUACAAACCCUCCACAGCGUGCUCUAUUAUUUUCCUCAUUUAUAAAAACAGAAACUAUGGACCGAGACAUGAAGUAACCUGUCCAAGGUCGGCCAAGUCUCAGAGACAGGGGCUUCAGACCCACCUGAGGCUCCUGACUCCACAUUAUGAACCCCGGGAUGGGCUGCAGCUCGGUCUGCUGGGAGGUUUCUGUGCUGGUUCAAAGAGGGUGGUACCUGACUGGCCUACCCAAUUUUAAUUUGUACUGAGCUUUAAUUUUCUAUUUGUGCUCAGGUUUAAUUUCCUCCUGGGAUCUGCUUCCCAGUGCUGUACUCUGUAUCUUUGCUUUCUUGUGUGAACAUUGUGACCGAUUUUCCCUGUUCUUCACGUGGGACACAUUCUCCCUGCUCUGUCUGUCUCUGUCCCUGUCUCUCUUUCUGUCUUUCUCUCUCACUGUGUGUCUCUCUGUCUCUCUCUCUCUUUUUUUUUUUUUUUGAGAUGGAGUUUCGCUCUUGUUGCCCAGGCUGGAGUGCAAUGGCACAAUCUUGGCUCACUGCAACCUCUGCCUCCCGGGUUCAAGCGAUUCUCCUGCCUCAGCCUCCUGAGCAGCUGGGAUUACAGGCAUGCACCACCACACACGGCUAAUUUUUUGUAUUUUUGUUAGAGACGGGGGGCUCUCCAUGUUGCUCAGGCUGGUCUUGAACUCCCGACCUCAGGUGAUCUGCCCACCUCAGCCUCCCAAAGUCCUGGGAUUACAGGCAUGAGCCACUGCGUCCAGCCGUCUUUGUCUCUUUUUCUACAUCUCUGUCUUUCUUCUCUGGUUGUUUUUCAACCAUCAGCUGGGUGUUUUCUCCCAUAACGUCUUGUUUGUUUGACUAUGAGGUUGACAGGUGGGUACAUGAACUCUAUAGCAGAAGGUGGACAGUCUGCACAUAGCAGAGGAUGGGUGAAUUUUUCUACCCCUUGCAGAGCACAGGAGAGCUGAGCAGAUGCCAGUGUCUGCUCCAGUGUAAGGAAGUCCAGGAAGUUCAGGUGGUGAGGUCACAGUGGAAAGCAGGACAGAUAGAGUUUAGGGGAAAUUAAGCAAAAAUACCACACUGUUAUUUCUUGACAUAUUAGUGGAAAGAGGAAGGGCCCAGAGAGAAGACAGAAAAUUAGAUGCAGGGGCUUGUUUUUUCUCUUGACUUGCCAACCCGCCCAACGCAGGGGCCAGAACUCAGGGUGGUGAGAUCUGGGAACAUUGCUGUGCGGAGAAGAUGUCCCUCCUGCUGCACGGGCCCCCAAGCACCACCUGGGGGAAGAGCCAUGUUUAAUUCACCUGGCAGUGCAGUGUGGCCAGGCAGAGAGGGAGGGCCUACCCUGUGCUUAUGAUCCCACCCCAGUUCCCCUGGGGUGUGCCCUGGCGGUGAACACCAGGAGGCUGCAGUGGGGCCCAACGUGAAAGGGAGGAGCAGCCUCACCGGGGCCAGAUGGGGCAGCAGCAGAUAUUCACAGAUGUCCCUGUGAGUAACCAGGGCAGAGGCCAGGGGUCUGGCCUUCCCUUUCUUGGAGCCCUGGGCCAGCUGGGCAAGGCGUUGAGAGAAAGAUUACCCGGUGACCUUUAUCAAAGCAGAGUAAGGAGGGCUUUAUUCAGAACCAUCACUGUAGGUACCAGGACCCCAGCGGUGGGAUUUUGUAGUAGGGGAAAGAAAAUGGGCUCGACGUUGAAUACAGCAUGAACAAGUGAGAAUGUUUGUUAUACAAACUAUAGGGUGGACUUUUUUUUUCUUUUUUUUAACUUUUUUUUACCUUUUAGUGUAAAACUGAACAUAGAAAAUAAAUUCAUGAAGAAGGGAUAUUUUCUGAGGGUGUCCAGGGCUGCCCAACACCUCGUCUACCUUCUCUGUCAUAGCCCCAUUUAAAACACUCUCUCUGGAUGAAUACACCAAACCUCACAGUCUUUGCUCUCUUGCUAGGAAGAGGAGCAAGAGCGUGUUUCACUCUUGGCUCCUGCUUACACACCUGCUGUCCAAUGGAAACUACUACUUAAGACAUUUAAAAAUAGUUGUGGUGAUAGCAUGUUGUGUUUUGGUUGGUGAUGCCAGUUAGUCUCUGAAAACUUUCUGUGAUGAGUGUAAAAUUCUACACCUUAAUCUCCUUUCUUGUAGGAUCUGGGAAGCAGUAUGCACUUGAUUGCACCAAAGAUUUUACGUUCAUAGAAAAUUUCUGGCAUCUGUGUGAAGAAAGUAAACUAUAUCUUCCAUUUAGACAAAUAAAAUAUCUUUUUGAUAAAA